AAGGAGGCUCGGCCCCAGCUACCCGCGGCGCCGCGCUCCUCCACGCUCCGGGAGGCCCCUGCAGGUGCCAUGACUCAGCAGCCCCAGGACGACUUUGACAGGAGCGUGGAGGAUGCCCAGGCAUGGAUGAAGGCUGUGCAGGACCAGCUGCAGGUCAAUGACAACACGCAGGGACCCCGCGCGGCCCUGGAGGCCAGGCUGUGGGAGACCGAGAAAAUAUGCCAGCUGGAGCCCGAGGGGCGUGUGAGGGUGGACCUCGUGCUACGGAUGGCUGAAGCCCUCUUGGCAUGCUGCCCUGGGGACCAGAAGCCCGGGAUCCUGGCCCGGCUGAAGGACAUCAAGGCCCAAUGGGAGGAGACAGUCACCUACAUGACUCACUGUCACAGCCGCAUCGAGUGGGUGUGGCUGCACUGGAGCGAGUACCUGCUGGCCCGAGAUGAGUUCUACCGCUGGUUCCAGAAGAUGAUGGUCACACUGGAGCCCCACAUCGAGCUCCAGCUGGGCCUGAAGGAGAAGCAGUGGCAGCUGAGCCACGCCCAGGUGCUGCUGCACAACGUGGACAACCAGGCGGUGCUCCUGGACCGGCUGCUGGAGGAGGCAGCCUCCCUGUUCAACAGGAUCGGGGACCCCAGCGUGGACGAAGAUGCCCAGAAGAGAAUGAAGGCUGAGUACGAUGCAGUGAAGGCCAAGGCCCAGAAGCGUGUAGAUCUGCUGGAGCAGGUGGCCCGGGAGCAUGAGGAGUACCAGGCAGGUGUGGACGAGUUCCAACUGUGGCUGAAGGCGGUGGUGGAGAAGGUGAAUGGCUGCCUGGGGCGGAACUGCAAGCUGCCCAUCACGCAGCGCCUCUCCACACUGCAGGACAUUGCCAAAGAUUUUCCCAGGGGCGAGGAGUCUCUGGAGACGCUGGAGGAGCAGUCUGCGGGUGUCAUUCGGAACACCUCUCCUUUGGGUGCAGAGAAGAUCACCGGAGAACUGGAAGAGAUGAGGAAAGUUCUGGAGAAGCUGCGCGCCCUCUGGGAGGAGGAGGAGGAGCGGCUGCGGGGCCUGCUCCGGUCCAGGGGAGCCUGGGAGCAGCAGAUUAAGCAGCUGGAGGCUGAGCUCAGUGAGUUCAGGAUGGUCCUGCAGAGGCUGGCCCAGGAGGGCCUGCAGCCUGCGGCGAAAGCGGGGACCGAGGACGAGCUGGUGGCACACUGGAGACGCUACUCGGCAACACGGGCGGCGCUGGCCUCGGAGGAGCCCCGGGUGGACCGGCUGCAAGCCCAGCUGAAGGAGCUCAUCGUCUUCCCUCACAACCUGAAGCCACUCUCUGAUAGUGUCAUCGCUACCAUCCAGGAGUAUCAGAGCCUGAAGGUGAAGAGCGCGAGGCUGCGCAAUGCCGCGGCGGUGGAGCUGUGGCAGCAUUUCCAGCGGCCUCUGCAGGAUCUGCAGCUGUGGAAGGCCCUGGCCCAGCGGCUCUUGGAGGUCACUGCCAGCCUGCCGGACCUGCCUUCCCUUCACACCUUCCUGCCCCAGAUCGAGGCAGCCCUGAUGGAAAGCUCCCGCCUGAAAGAGCUGCUGACGAUGCUGCAGCUGAAGAAAGACCUCCUGAUUGGCAUCUUUGGCCAGGAGAGAGCCACGGCACUCCUGGAGCAGGUGGCAGGUUCCAUGAGGGACAGAGACCUGCUGCAUAACAGCCUCCUGCAGAGGAAAAGCAAACUGCAGAGCCUGCUCGCUCAGCACAAAGACUUUGGAGCAGCUUUUGAGCCCCUGCAGAGGAAGCUCUUGGACCUCCAGGUCAGGGUCCAAGCCGAGAAGGGGCUUCAGCGGGACCUUCCUGGAAAACAGGCCCAGCUCUCAAGGUUGCAGGGGCUGCAGGAAGAGGGGCUGGACUUGGGGGCACAGAUGGAGGCUGCAAGGCCUCUGGUCCAGGAGAACCCCAACCACCAGCACAAAAUGGACCAGCUUUCCUCCGACUUCCAGGCCCUGCAGAGGUCUCUGGAGGACCUUGUGGACAGGUGUCGGCAGAGUGUGCAGGAGCACUGCACCUUCAGCCACCAGCUGCUGGAGCUGCGGCAGUGGAUCGUUGUGACCACGCAAAAGCUGGAGGCACACCGGGGAGAGGCGGGCCCGGGGGAUGCCGAGUCCCAAGAGGCCGAGUUUGAGAGGCUGGUGGCAGAAUUCCCGGAGAAGGAGGCCCAGCUGUCCCUGGUGGAAGCGCAGGGCUGGCUGGUGAUGGAGAAGUCUUCUCCGGAGGGUGCUGCCGUGGUGCAGGAGGAGCUCAGGGAGCUGGCAGAGUCGUGGCGGGCCUUGAGGCUGCUGGAAGAAAGUCUGCUGAGCCUCAUCAGAAACUGGCAUCUGCAGAGGAUGGAAGUGGAUUCGGGGAAGAAAAUGGUUUUCACCAACAACAUCCCAAAGUCAGGAUUUCUCAUCAAUCCCAUGGAUCCUAUUCCCAGGCAUCGUCGACGCGCAAAUCUUCUACAGGAAGAAGAAGGGAGCCAUGAAGAUUUCUCCCAGCUCCUGAGGAACUUUGGGCAGUGGUUGCAGGUGGAAAACUCCAAGCUGGUUAGAAUCAUCGCAAUGAGAACUUCUACAGCUGAGGACUUGAGGACCAGAAAAUCGAAGCUGCAGGAGCUGGAGGCUCGGGUGCCAGAAGGUCAGCAUCUCUUUGAGAACCUCCUUCGUCUCGGGCCAGCAAGGGGGACCUCGGAUGAGCUGGAAGAUCUGCGCUACCAGUGGAUGCUGUACAAGUCCAAGCUGAAGGACUCUGGCCACCUGCUGACACAAAGUUCUCCAGGGGAGCCGACUGGAUUCCAAAAGACUCGGCGGUGGCGAGGACUGGGCUCCCUCUUCCGGAGGGCGUGCUGUGUGGCGCUCCCACUGCAGCUGCUUCUGCUGCUGUUCCUCCUCCUGCUGUUCCUGCUCCCAAUCAGGGAAGAGGACCGCAGCUGCACCCUGGCCAACAACUUCGCCCGCUCCUUCACGCUCAUGCUGCGCUACAAUGGCCCACCACCCACCUAACCCACUGGGGCACACAGGUGACUUUCUCCUCCAACCUCCAUCAGUCCCAGGGCCCCUCCUGAGGAUGCUCGCCAGGGAAACUGGAAACAGGGGCAGGGCAAAGACUGCAGAGCUGCAUCCAUAUCAGUGCUGUGUCAGCGUUCCCAGAAGACACUUACUUUUUAUACAGUGUUGUCUUAGUCUAUUUAUACUAAAUGUGUACUACAUGUGACUAGGGAAUAAUGUCUAGAAUUUUUAUAUGAUCUGUAUGUAAAUGCUCAGUAUGUAUAAUUUCAUAUACGAGUUCUAUUUGGAGUUGGGAAAAUUCCUAGCAAUGGCUCCCUCCAAUGGGAUUUUGUGGUAUUGUUGACUUGGUCUGCAGUCAACCCUAGAAAGCAAGAACAAUAACAUGUCACUUUCAUGGCAACCUCUUCUCCAAAGCGAAUCCCAGAAUUCAGAUGUAAUGAAAGGCCUCUGAGCUGCAACGUGGAAGAGCGCCAUAGACCCUCACUUGGUGCCCAGCGACUCUUGCUUUAUGCGUAAUGAGAACAAGUAUGCUUGUCUAGUUUUAACAACCACAAAGAGUAGCUGCCACGUGUCAGAAGUAGAAAUGGCAAUGACCAGAGGCAGGUUCAAUGAUAGCAGUGACAAGUGACAGAGUGAUAUCGAGGGAGAAAAAGAAGAGCUGCAGAGAGCAGAUCCCCGAACUAAGAAAGCACAGCUGUGUGGAGGCAUUGCAUGCCGGAGCCCUAACCCCAGCUCUCAGCGGCUUCUGAUCACACAGACCUAUGAGGACUGUCCCUGGUGAUGACACCGAGCCCCCAUGAAACGGUGAGAUCCUGCUCUGUGUGUUUCAUUCAGGGAGAAAGGGAAGAAGACAAGCUUGAUUUUUAAGAUUUCCAUGCAGAAUGGUGAGGCACACUCGGUGGGCAGCACCCACUGGCAGUGCCCAGGAAAGAUGUGUUUCCUCUGUUGCUCCUGGACUGAGUUUUCAUCGUCGAGAGCUCGAGCUGCAGGUGAGAAGGGAAGCAUCUGCCACGCCAGGGGCCAGGGAUCGAGGGUCCAGGACAGAGGUGAGAGAAUCUGCUUUGGAGUUCAGCCUGUCUCAAGGGCUCUCCUUCCGCUUCCCAGAAAAGACUCUGGAGACAGCAGGUCUAUGGGGCCAAGAAGGUCUCAUGUGCAUCCCCAUAUGGGACUAGGGCCCAGGCCACCCAAAACCAGGCCCUCUCCAGCCAGGUGUAGGCGAGCUGGGCUCCAUGCACCACCUGGGCUGGGGCCGCGGUGACUCCAUGUGAGUUCCCGAGGCCAGAAACUCAUCCCUUCCUUGCCAGGGAACUCUGGGAUGGUUCCUAAGUGCUCUACAACUGGAUCAUGUUUUUCCUAAAUCAACACUAAAUUUUCCCCUUUAAAAAAGUACUUAAUGCCCACUCUCUACAAAUGGAUUUUGUCUGUUCAACUACAAAUACGAGGGGAUUUCCUCGGACCUUCUGUCCGGCUUUGGAAUCAUAAGGUAUUAUAGACCCAGAAAGGCCCUUUAAGUAGAGGGGAAACUGAGGACCUAAGAGGGCCUGAUACCCAGCACCAUUGCUGUCUCACACACACUGACCCUUUGCCUUUCACUGUGAGCUCUGCCCUUGGGGACCCGGGUCCUAGGCAACUAGGACAUUUCACCGGCAGGAAACCCGUGCUGCCAAGGAGAGCCCUUGGGGCUGACUCAGAAAGCGUACUUUUUUUUUUCUUUUAACUCGUCUGUAUUUGUUACAACUUUAAGCAGAAUGUGACUUGGGCACUAUAUUUCCAUCCACAAGCCUGGCUCUGAGUUAUUAUUAUUAUUGUUAUUAUAAUUAUUUUGAGAUGGAGUUUCGCUCUUUUUGCCCAGGCUGGAGUGCAGUGGUGCGAUCUCGGCUCACUGCAACCUCCGCCUCCCAGAUUCAAGCGAUUCUCCUGCUUCAGCCUCCCAAAUAGCUGGGAUUACAGGCAUCUGCCACCAUGCCCAGCUAAUUUUUGUAUUUUUAGUAGAGUUAGGGUUUUACCAUGUUGGCCAGGCUGGUCUCGAACUCCUGACCUCAGGUGAUCCGCCCACCUCAGCGUCCCAAAGCACUGGGAUUACAGGCAUGAGCCACCAUGCCUGGCCAUUUUUUUUUUUUUUUGAAUAGCUUUAUGAUAAGCUGUAGGCUUAUAAUUAUGCUCCUCCAAACAACACUUUUCUUUGGAAAACAAGCCCUGUAGACUCUCCAUCCUUCCAUCAAGUUCCUUCCCUCAAGCUGCUUCAGUUUAACUUAUUUCUACAAGACUAGUACAUGCAGAAUUGGCAACUACAGGGGAUGAAAAGUUCAAAAAGUAGAUCCUACAACCCUGUGACUUGGUUUCCAAAUAUCUAGAGAAAUUUGUGAUUUCAUGGAAGAAGAGAAAGCACACUUUUCUCCAGAUAUCUGGAAACCAAGCCAUAGGGCCGUUCUCUGCAGGCGACCACCUUACUGGAAAAUCAGGAGCUGAGUGAGCCCAGGCAGCCAAGCCCAGAUGUCCAGUCCUGGAAGUCAGAGCAGUGGCAGGGUGGGUGGGUGGGGGGGCCUUGCCAGGUGUCCACUUUCCUAUGUCACAGGUGAGAAAGCUGAGGCCCAGAAUGGGGAAGAAACUGAUCCAUGGCCACACAGUGAGAGGCAGCAAGGCCAGAGCCCAACUGGCCACCAUGGCCCUCAGGUGGUACCCUGCUCAUUGUGGUAUGAUCCGCUCAUGUCAGCAACUACAUGAAAAAAACAGCCACUGGGCAUGUAUGCAGCCUGUCACAUAUACCACAUGUUGGGGAAGGAGAAGCUGGAACAUGCGGGCGGGGGUGGGAAUAUCUACCUAUAUUUUUUAAAUUUUGAUAAUGAUGCCAUCAAGUCUGUUUGUUUGCAUAACUGUUUUUUAAAAAAGAAUUGAUAUUUUCAGUAUUUUCAUAUAAAUAUACUUGUAAUAUAACGUAACAGCCCAGUUACUGGUGCUUCCAAGCACAAGUGCAAUCUCCUUUGCUUAAAGGAGAGCCAGGCAAUUAUUCUUAUGACUUUAGUUUCCAGCCUCUUUAACAGCCAUGCAGAGCUUUAAGGUGCUACUUGAGAAAGGUGGCGCUGUGGCGUGUGUGUGUGUGUGUGUGUGUGUGUGUGUGUGUGUGUGUGUGUGUCAGAGAGAGAGAGAGGAGGGAAGGAGAGGAGGGAGAAAGGACCACCAGUGGGUCGGUUGAUGAAUUAGUUAUCCCUGCUUACCUGUCCCUCCCACCCCUUUCUUUCUUAGCCCGUUCUCUGCAUGUGGAAAGGCACAUGCAGCACCCAGAGGGUGUUUAAAAAGAAAAGCUGGGAGCGGGAGGGAUGGGCAGGUACUGACAGCAGACGAGGCGAGGAGACCCUGGGAGGUGCCCAGUGGUGGCGGGACAGAGGGAACACCGACAAGGGAGACAAAGAAUGUGCUCGUUUGGUGCUCGUGGGUGCUUGAGCCCCUUGGGCGGCACUUUGCAGCCUUGCUUUAUGUAAUUCCCACAUCGACACCUGCCCCCAGGGUUUGAUACUGUUUUACCCCCAUGUUUGAGAUGGAACCCUGAGGCUUAAAGAUAUAAAGACCCUUGCUCAUGCUGAAGUGGGUCCAAACCCACAACAUGGGGCAAUGAGGACCCCAAAGCCCAGGCUGGAGGGGGGCUUCAGGCUGGUUCUACCAGGUUGCAGUCUCUGUAGCCUCUGGGAAUGGAGUUCCCUGGGCAAGCAGGCAGAACUCUCUGCCCAUCAGCUCGCCUGGGACAUGGCCAGAGCGGAGCAUCCAAAUGUUUCCCUGAGGGACUGCCCUCAGCUCUGAGAUGAGUCACCACCAGCAGCACAUUCCCUUGGGCCAUCUAUCAUUAUCUUCACAUUGCUCACCUGGAAGAUGAGCCCCUCUAAUGUCUCAUGAUGAGGUCCUCGGUCAUGAAUGACAGAACUCCACACCCCCAAUGCCCAGCACAGGAUAAGAGCUUCAGCUGUGGUUUGUUGAAUUACAUUAAAAACCCAAAGGCAAAUGUGUUUCCUGACACCCGACUCCCUUCCAGAGGAAAUGGGUCAAGGAUGACCUGACCCAAUUCCAUCUCUCAGGCCCCGUUUGCUUCAGGCAGCUGGCUGGAGUUCCCUGCAGGGACCGGGGGUCCAAAGAUGCUUGUCUCCGGGCAUCUUCAGGGGAAGGAAGCUGGGGACCCUCUGCACCCUGGGGGCCAAGGAGAAUGACAGGCAGAGGGCAGGAAAAGGCCUGAAGGCGGGUGGUUUGUGCUGGAUGUUCCCUAAUGGAUUUUACAGCUGGCAAACUGGGACCGGUGGCAUCAUCCUGCCCUGCCUUGCAGGGGAUGGGAGGCUGGGGCUGCCCACAGUUAGGGAGUAAAGAGGGGAUCUUAUCUCUUCCAUUAGACUGGAGCCAGGCCUGACUGGGAAGCUGGGAGGCUUUGCAGAAGCUUUGAGGAACUGCACUUUAUGGUGGUCUGGCUGGAGAGGGCGGACGGGGAAGUGGGCCAGAGGGAGUCAAAGGCCAGAGGUGAUGUCAGGCUUGAUUUACUGAACUGUGUGCUUAAAAGUGGUUAAGAUGCUAAAUUUUAUGUUAUGUUUAUUUUACCACAAUUUGAGGGUGAGAGGAGAGAGUGAGAGCAAAAGAGACAGAGAGAAGAGAGAGAAAAGGAGGAAGGGAGGGAGGGAGGGAGGGAUAGAGAGAGAGAAAAAGAGAAUGGGAAUGGCAGGCUGUGCCUUCAUGGUUCCCAACUUUCCUCUGAGGACAAGCGCUAGUGGCAAAGCUUUCACUGACCAAAGGCAAGUGAAACAAUACGAGGGAACAACUUGAGUUUUUCUUUCCAUAGGAUUUAUUUUGCCCAAACGCUGGCUCUUCAUUCUGGGAUUAUGUCCCUCCUACUUCAAGGGUGCUCAAUGGCCUUUAGGAAAUGAGGGAUAGGUAAAGGUGGCUCUGUCUUCUUUGAUGGUUUCUAUUGUGUUUUGGGAGCCCUCAUUGGACAAAAUAAAAAGUUGCCAACUCUAUGUUGGUUUUGCUCCCCAUACAGUAUUCUUCCUGGAAAAACAUGCUGUCUGAAAGUUUGGGAACCCAGGAGAUGGUUGGGAGAAGAGAGCAGCUUGAGGAUUGCUUAGUGCAGGAGUCCCCGAGGGAGAGAAGGAAAGAGAAAUGGGAAGAGGGACAUCGUGGAAAGUUGUGGCAACUGGGUUCAGGGGAGGCCAGGAGCCUGCCAGCUGUGGCCUCUAAAAAAAUAAAACCCAGGUGCUCACUGGCCCUGCCUUCCCACUGGCCAUUCGGAUGCUGUCCGGGGUCUGCGGCUUUCUCUCCCCUGGUUGGUGGGCAGAAGUGCCCUGUGCCUCUUUGCAUCUUAAUCCAAUGCAACAAGCAUUCUCCAGCCUGUGCCAGGCUUUGUGCUGGGAGAUUCGGGGUGAACAAAGCCCAGUCCCUGCCCUCAGGGAGCUUGCAGACGAAGAAAAGGGUUUGUGCCAUUGAAGAUGCCCAACGGGAUUGCAGUCAUUGCCCUUGACUUUGCCCAUCUGCCUUUCCAGAGGGGGCAGGCCCACUGUCACAGAAACUGGAAGAGCCACACAGGGGAGACAGUGGGAGAGCUCGGAACAGGGCAUGAGAGUGUCUUGCUGCCUCUUGGAGGCCACCAUUGUGACUAUGAACCAUACCGGGCAGAGGAAGUGGGUCAAGGAGGCCAGGGCAGCUGGGCCGGGCAGGGAGAGGACCUGGGCAUGGCAGAGGAGGGGAAAAUAGACUGACCCAGCCUCAGGAGGUCAGAAGUGUGUUGGGCUGUGCUGGGUCACAGAACAACACAGCUUGGGAGGCUCCUGGAGGCUUCAAGGGGAGGCUUAAGGCUAAGGCUGUGGAUGUUGAUUGUCGUGUCCAUUACUAGCCCAAUUAUUAGUCUGUCUUCCUGGUAAAAAUGUGUGGUUGGAAAUGCCAAACUGAGAAGCCCACUUUUCCCCACUGGGGAUCAUCUGGGUUGGCGUGUCCAUGCUCAAGGAUAAUCUCUUGCCCUUUCCUGCCCCCUGCCUAGGAUUUCUCCCCAGAGGAGAGGAGCUGAGGGACCCCCCCAGGGAGGCUGUGCCUGUGGCUGUCACCCUAUGAUGCCAGCGGCUUCCUUUGGAUUCUGUAAUCAGAGUGUUUUUCACCGGUGUCUGCAGUGAUUGCCAGGAAGCCUCUGUGUCCAUAGCCCAGCGGGAUCCUGCCCUAAUUCCCUCUCUCAUGGGCACUCAGCUAAUUCUCACCCCAAUCUCAUUGUCACCAGUCUAGGUCAGCAUUGGAGGGAGGUGUGGGCAACUACAGCCCUUGCUGCUUCCAAGACAGACAUCAAAAUAGUUGAUCACCAACCUUUCCCACUCCCCACUCUCUGACCCAAUGGACCUCACAGUCCUCAAAACUACUCCAAGCUACUGCCAAUCAAUCAUUUUCUUAUGUGAGCAAAACCUGUUUGACAUCCUUACACCUGUACCAGCCCUCUCAGAAAGCUCUCAAUUCUGGUCUCCUUUUCUUUUUUCUUUUUUUUUUUUUGAAUUUAUGUUAAAAUUAGGAUGUUCCCAAUCAAAAAAUCAUUUUUCCUUCAUCUAGUAAUUGGGUGAGACAAACUAGCCCCAGAAAGCAGACAAUGGGAUGAACUGCCAAGUAGGACUUUUAGGGGAGGCAAAAUGGAUUAGGAAAUGCUAAGUUCUCUGUUGAAGGAGGAUACCUGGAUUCUUCAGGCUGUCAGAGUUGGAGGGCUUCCAUAGACUGUCUUGUUCCAACUUUGUACCCAUUUUACAGGUUAGGACUCUGAGACCUCAGCAGUUCUUGUUUGGCCAGUGAGCUCAGGGAGUUAGUUCCAGGAGUGGGGGUCGGUCUCUGCACCCACUGGAUGACAGCUUGAUACUGCUCAGCACUAGACAGGGUUGAGUUGGAACUCUGCUGCUGAUGGGCUGUGUGACAUUGGUCCAGUUCCUUACCACCUCCCCCCACCUAUUGGUAAGGAGGGAAGUCAGCCCUGGAGCGUUCAGUGCUCCCUGAAAUAUUAGGUAUCCUAGGAUUGUGCGCGUGGGCUCGCAUCUGGAAGAGAAAUCCCUAGAUUCAGCCACGAGUAACAGAAUCCCUCCUCCCCCGACCAACUUUGGCUUAAACCAGUCAGAGACUUUACUUUUCUCUCCUCCUGAGAAGUCUAGAUAUAGGCGGUUGCUGGCAUCGUCUCCUCAGGUUAUGGAUGUCAGAGCCAAGGCUUUGCAACUGUCCUUCCUUUAUAUCACAGUCACUUCAUGGCCCAGGAUGCUUGCUGUACCUCCAAUUUUUCAUCUGGGUUCCAGGUAGGAAGAAGGGGAGUGAACUAGACGAAUCUGCCCUCCUCAUUAGCAGCUUUCCCAGAAGCUCCACCAGCCACUUCCGUUCUCAUCUCAUUGGCCAGGACUGUGUCACAUGUUUUCCCCCACAUCUGCAAGGAGUCUGGGAACAUGUGCCCCAAAAAGAUGGGGGCUCUUCUAGUAAGAAUGAAGGGUAGGGUGGCUUGGAGUGGCACUUCGCUGUCUCUGCUACAAUUGGAGGAGAAAACCAGAGUUUGUCCUGACCCUCCAUGCCUUGGCUGUAUGCUCCUUGUGUGGAACUCGAAGGCAUCAUCCUUGCAGUGUGAGAGUGACCUGCCACCACGGCCUGCCACCUCCUCUCAGGGGACCCUGAGUCCUUCAGGUCUACCCAAAGGCAUUGUAGACAUUCUUCCUGCAAGGCUUGGGAACCGACAAAUAGAUCUGCCCAGCUUGCCAGAGUUUUUGUGCAGGAACAGCCCCUCCCGUCUUUGUCCUGGCGGUGAGCACCCAGGGCUAAGCUUUUGAACACUUUCUUUGUGUUUGGAUUCAGCCCAGGCAAUGCAUAUUUGCUUUCAUUUCUUCUUGAGCUUGAGGAGCUCCUGGGUGCAAAUCUUGGAAAAUGAGGAUCUCUGAGCCUUUCCAGGCCAGCUCUUUGUUUUGUAGCAGACAAUUGAGGCUUUGAAAAGGAAAGUGGGUGGGGGCACCCCACAGGUGGCCCUCAUCACCCAAUUGCCAGUGCCUGCAGGCUGCUUCAGCAGAGGCCCAGAGUCAAAGAGGACUUAAAACCAGCUGUCGUUUCUCCCUUAGCUUCUGUGUAUGAGAGAAACGACUUCUGUUUUUCAAAGUAAGAACAAGGAGGAAUUUGUUUCUAAAAGAACAUUAAAACACAGGCUCGUGGUCUAAAAGCAAAUGGUUCAGCAGGAUGUUCAGGGCCUUAAAGCACAGUCAGCAGGACUCAGCAUCUCCCAGCACCUGCUCUCCGGUUGUCAUGGUAACAUCAUCCCCAACCCAACCACCUUGUCCAGCCGAGAGACAGCAAUCAUAAGGAGGGACCUCGGUUUCCCCCGAGGAUCCUGGGCUUCCUUUCUGAAACGCUUGCUUCUGAGCUCAGCAACCAGGAACACCAGGCCAGCCCAUCCCCAGCACCUCUGUGGAGAUGAGGGACAAAGUCCUACAGUCCCUCUUCCUGUUCUGAUGAGAAAGGGAGGGAAGAAAACAUACCCCGAGCGCCUGCAAUAUGGUCAUGACACUUUCAAAAAGCCUGUGCUAUGGAGUCAUGAUCAGAAACCAGAGUGUGGAGAGGGUCAGCAGCCUGCCUCAGAGCAGCCAGCUAGGCGGGGAGUGGUAAAUUUGGGACUUGUACCCAGGCAUGACUGGCUCCGAGCCCAGUGCUCCACUCUAUGGAAUGUUCCCUGGGCCUCAGUUGCUUUCCUUUCCUUUGCAGGCCGCGGGCUGCUGCCACUCUGGCAGCUGGUGAGUUAGCUGGAGGGCAACAUUCCAAAGCAGGGGCAGCAUGCUGCUUUCCUCCUGUGCCCACUCCUGCGGGGAAGUCCGUUGACUCCCACCGCUGAAGGGAGCUGGCAACACCAGGAUGAGGUCCCAGGGGACGGGAGCAGGUACCCACUGUCUGUCUACCUUCCCACUGGAAAAGCACGGACAGGCCAGCCCUUGCGGGGGCAGGCAGAGGACAGAGUUGGCUUUGCGCGGUCUCUGCCUGCUGAGCAGUUCCAAUUCCUCUCAUGGGAGAAACAAGGAGGCAGUCGCUUGUGCAUGUUCCAGAAGUUUUACUGGGGAGGAGGAAGCGGACAGAGGAAGCUGUGUGUGCAUGUGAAGGGGUGGGCAGGGUGGGAGGGAUGCACGCGUAUGUGAGCAUAGCAUGUGUGAGUACUACACACAUCUCCAUGCAGAAGCACAACUGGGCAGCCCUGGCUUCCAGCUCUGGGCUUCAGCACAACAGACACCAGCCUGUGGUCUCUCAGAAGCCAGGGAGACCACAUCGGGCUCAGGACGUUUUACCCAAAGUCCAGAGUUUUUAUGCCUCUCCCUGGCAUUCUCCAUAAAGAAGGGAAGGUCAGAUGACCCCUUAGAUCUGUGUCAUCUGGGAAUUUCCUUGGGCUGGUUUAGACACGAUGCCCUCUUUUUCUCAGGAUAGCAGAUAACCUGCUUUGAAAGAGGGCUUAAUUCUGUGGGUCCUAAAUUUUCUCCUUUCUCUCUCUCUUUCUGUGUGUGUGUGUUGGGAAAAUGGCAAGUUUCCAAUACCAGCUUUGGAGGAACGAUUACGUUUUCCCUCCAAUUUCAAGUCCGAAAGACCAGAGCCCUCAUUCCAAAGCCCCCCACCCAGAUGGAUUUUUUCGUUUCAUUUGUCAUCCGUCCCAUGGGAGGGCCCCAUGUCUCCUCAGAACCCAUCCUGGAGGCAGCAGGUCGGGUAGAGUGAGUUUGGCCUGCUCAUGACCUCCACCCCUGAGAUUGUGAACAAGGAUGUCUGGGGCGAUGCUGAGAAUGUUUUUGAAGCUGCUCCCAGAUGACGCUGAUGAUCACACCAGAUUGAGUGCUGCGAUCGCCUUGAGUCCAACCUCUGCAUAAACGAGGUUCUCAUAAACAAGUUCACUCUACCCUAAGCUAAGUCUAUGUGAGCAAACCCACUUCAUCCUUUGUACCUGGAGACCUGGUUACACUAACCUGAUACUGACCUGUUCAUGUAGCUGGAAUGGUGUGUUUCAUGCAGUGUGGACCAAGCAAUGGCAUGGGGUGUGUGUGUGUGUGUGUGUGUGUCUGUGUGUGUGUGUUUGUGUAUGCGUUCACACUUGUGUGUGUAUAUGUGCAUGUAGAUGCUGCAUAAAUGAUUUUUGAUGUCAAAGACAAACACAUUCCAUUGUUUUAAAUAUUCUAUUAUGUAAACAAUACGCAGAGGGACCAUAUCUACUCUUGUCAUAUUAUUUGUGAUGGUAAAACAUGCAUUUGCAAUAAAUUAAGCUUUCUGGGAAGGCAAGCAGUAUUGGAGCCAAACGACUGUCUCGGAACAUGUGUGUGUUAUCUCGGUUCAUAUCAAGUCCAAAGCUAAUGGAGCCUUCCCCGCCAUCCAGGGAGGAACACCAGGACCCCGGAGUUUCUUCUUAGUGCUAUAUUUUAAAGUUGCAUUGACGUUUUCCUCCCCUUCCUUUUGUGCAAGUUGGAAGUAGCAGUGUUCUAAAAGAUGGUUUGACGUUUUUGCUGUUGUUUUAUGUUUUUAAAAAUGUAUCUGCUUUGUGUUUGGAAAUAAAAAUCUCUAUUUUGGUCUAUGAAA